ACCCGACCCCUCCAGGCUGUAAAACGGAAAGGUUCGGAAUUUGCCUCUGCGCCGUCUUUUUUUGCCUGUUACCUGUGACGUCCUUGGAAUUUAUUACUGUUAUCUCCAUUUGAGUUCUAGCUGCUCUUUUUAUAUGAUGGAGUUGAAUCUUUUGCCUAUCAUAUGAUUAUUCUUUUGGCUCUUUACAAUGUAGCUAGGAAAAAUUUGUCUUUGAUGUGAUAUAAUAUCUGAAUCCCUGGAGGAACUACAGUCAUGCAUCGCUGAACAGCAAGGAUAUAUGUUCUGAAAAAUGCAUCAUUAGUCUAUACCAUAAUCUAUAACAGUGGUACCAGUGGCCCCGGUAGUUAAUAUCACAGUCAUGAAGACUCACAGCCUAUUGUAGCUAGCAAGAGGGAAUCCAUGACUCCUCUGGGAAGAAAGGUGAUCAUCUUUUCUUUGACAUUGGAAGCAGAAUCUGAAACUUUCUGAGGAGAGCAUUUGAGCUUCAGAUUUCUAACAGCCUCUUUGCAACAAAAUAGACCAGUAGCUGAAGGCAACUGCAAUCCUUCAUGAUGUUUCCCUUGGCCAGAAAUGCACUAAGCAGUCUCAAGAUUCAAAGCAUUCUGCAAAGCAUGGCAAGACAUAGCCAUGUAAAACACUCACCAGAUUUUCAUGAUAAAUAUGGUAAUGCUGUGCUAGCCAGUGGAACUGCUUUCUGUGUUGCUACAUGGGUGUUUACAGCCACUCAGAUUGGAAUAGAAUGGAACCUAUCCCCUGUUGGCAGAGUUACCCCAAAAGAGUGGAAACAUCAGUAACCAUCACAGUUGCUGUAAUGACAGAAUUGUUUAAAAAACCAACUUGUCAUGUAAGCACUCUACUGCUUAUUAAAAUAUAGCACAAUUGAAAAAAUAAAAUGUGUUUUAAAUCUUUAAAAA